GUUUUCCGUGAGAGACGUAGAGCUGAGCGACCCAGCCCGCGAGCGAGGUGAGAUGCCGGUGGCCGUGGGUCCCUACGGACAGUCCCAGCCAAGCUGCUUCGACCGUGUCAAAAUGGGCUUCGUGAUGGGUUGCGCCGUGGGCAUGGCGGCCGGGGCGCUCUUCGGCACCUUUUCCUGUCUCAGGAUCGGAAUGCGGGGUCGAGAGCUGAUGGGCGGCAUUGGGAAAACCAUGAUGCAGAGUGGCGGCACCUUUGGCACAUUCAUGGCCAUUGGGAUGGGCAUCCGAUGCUAACCAUGGUUGCCAACUACAUCUGUCCCUUCCCAUCAAUCCCAGCCCAUGUACUAAUAAAAGAAAGUCUUUGAGUA